UCCUAAAGAUUGGCUUCGGAAAACUGAGGUACAGAAAAUUAAUAAUUAAUGUUCACAUGCUGUCAGGAAUACUCAGAUGCGAGGGGGCAUCUGAGUCCAUUUUUUGGGCACUUUUGCUUUCUGGGAUGCUCUCGUGCCUAAUGACAGCCCUGCAGCUGCCUGCAUCCUUUCUGGUGGGGGUCAGGCCUGAUGCGAUGAGAUCUGAUGUGUUCAGUGACCUUCUAGUUAAGGUCCUGGGCCGGCCUUGUAUUGCUGGGGCUUUUAUGUGUGCUGGGAUUAACACCAGUGACUGCUGUUAUCAGCAUAGAUGGCGUUUGUUCUCAUUUCAGGACCGUAUCUGAGUAAUUGCAUCCAUUGUGAUGUGCCACCAAAGAGAAAAGUACUUUGGUCAUACUCGACUAUGUAAACUAAGUAUUUUAAGUUAAGGCCAAUUCCAAUGCAUUUUAUUACAAUUCAGCAUGAAACAGUUAACACGGACCAGUAACAGUAGAGUGAAAUUAGCAUGAAUAGAACCAACAUUCUUUUCCACAUAUGUAAUAAUAAGGGCACCCAAGCAGAUGUUGUACGGUCCCAGGGAAGACCACACACCUUACAUUUCCAGGCUUACUGCACUUGGGAUUAAGCCAAGGCAUCCAAAGAAAGAAAAUUUUUUUUUUUUUUUUUUUUGCCAGGCUGGAGUGCAGUGGUGCGAUUUCGGCUGACUGCAACCUCCACCUCCCGGGCUCCAUACCUGGCUAAUUUUUGUAUUUUUAGUAGCAAUGGGGUUUCACCAUGCUGGCCAGGCUGGUCUCAAACUCCUGACCUCGUGAUCUGCCCGCCUUGGCCUCCCAAAGUGCUGGGAUUACAGAUGUGAGCCACUGCGCCUAGCCUGAAAAUAAUGUUUAACUCCCAUUUAUAUGUUAGGCUGCUCAGAUAUAUUAAACACAUACACACACAACACACACACACACACACAUACACACUGCACAAGGAAACAGAGGGACAAAGCAGGAAGUCCAAGUUUCCAUUAAACCAGUCUUUAAAUGGUUAAAUUUAGUAGGAAAUAAAGGCAUCCUUAAUAGAAGUUGAGAAGCACAAUUCAAUAGUGACACCUAAAAAAAAAUUAAGACUUGAUUAGUUGAAUAAAAUCAAUUGUGAACAUUGCUCAGUUACUGGUGAUGCUACAGGAAAAAAAAAGUGAUGCCAGGAUAGAUUUGUUAGGCUUGUUUAAAAAAUACAUAAAAUUGUUCAUUAAUAAGACUUUAAUAUCCAGUUUUUAUGUCUGUGAUUAAAUAUCAUUUUUUAUUUUUAAAUGGUAUAGUUUUUAAAUUUUGAAACAAUUAAUUUUGCAUAAAUAUUUGUCUAUGUACAUAUAUACAUGUGUAUUCACAUAUAUAUAUGAAGGACACUUAGCUAUCUUAUUUACUGAAGCUAAAGAAGUAGGUCCUUAAAAAGCCAUUGACAGGUCUUGAGUUUGCAACGUGACUGUGAAACAGGCAUCCUUGUUACUCACACGUUUGCUGAAAGGAUAACAGAAAGCCCUCGAUAGAAAAAUCUCACUAGAUUGUUUAUAAUUUGUUGAUAUUUGGAGUAUCUUGAGUGGUAAACUUUAAAUGUGGAUUUAUUUUUUCUUUCCUUUUAGGAUUUGGAUCUCUCCAAUCUUUUUUAUGAUUAAUUGUUCAGUGUUUAUGCAUUAUUGCGAAGUGAUAAUGAAAAUGCUCAAACUCAGGGUCCUGCAGGCACUGUGGGGGAGGCAGUGGGGACGUGAGGGGAUUACAGAUCCAGUAGAAGCCCCCCGACCCCCAUCUGCUUCCACCCCAUCUCCUUCCAGAACACCACCGAUAGCCACACCGAAGAGUUCUCCCAUUUGCUGGUUCCCGGACAAAAAAGCUGCUGAUCCCUUGAGCACACUGCAGUGAAGCUCCCAGCUGACAUGUCCUGUCCAUGUAAACAGAACUUCCUCCAUCAUGCAACCAAGAUCACCACGUGCACAGUUCACCGUAGGUUCACUCUCCUACAAGACUCCAACGCUGCCACUGACCUAACAGGAGGUGGAGCUCAGGCGGUGAUGUUCGCUCACCUGCUGCUCACCUCCUGCUGCGUGGCCCAGUUCCUAACAGACCACAGACGGAUCUGCUGGGGACUCCUGCAUAUAAAGUCUGCCAUCAUGGAUGUUCUCGCAGAAGCAAAUGGCACCUUUGCCUUAAACCUUUUGAAAACGCUGGGUAAAGACAACUCGAAGAAUGUGUUUUUCUCACCCAUGAGCAUGUCCUGUGCCCUGGCCAUGGUCUACAUGGGGGCAAAGGGAAACACCGCUGCACAGAUGGCCCAGAUACUUUCUUUCAAUAAAAGUGGCGGUGGUGGAGACAUCCACCAGGGCUUCCAGUCUCUUCUCACCGAAGUGAACAAGACUGGCACGCAGUACUUGCUUAGGAUGGCCAACAGGCUCUUUGGGGAAAAGUCUUGUGAUUUCCUCUCAUCUUUUAGAGAUUCCUGCCAAAAAUUCUACCAAGCAGAGAUGGAGGAGCUUGACUUUAUCAGCGCCGUAGAGAAGUCCAGAAAACACAUAAACACCUGGGUAGCUGAAAAGACAGAAGGUAAAAUUGCGGAGUUGCUCUCUCCGGGCUCAGUGGAUCCAUUGACAAGGCUGGUUCUGGUGAAUGCUGUCUAUUUCAGAGGAAACUGGGAUGAACAGUUUGACAAGGAGAACACCGAGGAGAGACUGUUUAAAGUCAGCAAGAAUGAGGAGAAACCUGUGCAAAUGAUGUUUAAGCAAUCUACUUUUAAGAAGACCUAUAUAGGAGAAAUAUUUACCCAAAUCUUGGUGCUUCCAUAUGUUGGCAAGGAACUGAAUAUGAUCAUCAUGCUUCCGGACGAGACCACUGACUUGAGAACGGUGGAGAAAGAACUCACUUACGAGAAGUUCGUAGAAUGGACGAGGCUGGACAUGAUGGAUGAAGAGGAGGUGGAAGUGUCCCUCCCGCGGUUUAAACUAGAGGAAAGCUACGACAUGGAGAGUGUCCUGCGCAACCUGGGCAUGACUGAUGCCUUCGAGCUGGGCAAGGCAGACUUCUCUGGAAUGUCCCAGACAGACCUGUCUCUGUCCAAGGUCGUGCACAAGUCUUUUGUGGAGGUCAAUGAGGAAGGCACGGAGGCUGCAGCCGCCACAGCUGCCAUCAUGAUGAUGCGGUGUGCCAGAUUCGUCCCCCGCUUCUGCGCCGACCACCCCUUCCUUUUCUUCAUCCAGCACAGCAAGACCAACGGGAUUCUCUUCUGCGGCCGCUUUUCCUCUCCGUGAGGACAGGGCAGUCUUGGUGUGCAGCCCCUCUCCUCUCUGUCCCCUGACACUCCACAGUGUGCCUGCAACCCAAGUGGCCUUAUCCGUGCAGUGGUGGCAGUUCAGAAAUAAAGGGCCCAUUUGUGGGAUGCCGCAUUCA